AUGUUCAUCACCCUCAGAGAUUGCCCCACUGGCAUAUGUGGACAAGUCAACGCUCAGAAAGGUUACCUCGACGCGUCACACAUAGUGUCCCCACCCCGCCGCCCCGCCCCUGGGCGCCGGGGACUCGGCUCAGACGCGCAGAGGGAAGGCAGGGCGGCUGCAGAGAGCAGAGCCGAAGAGGAAUCGAAAGCUUCAGAAACGCGGUGUGACCAGCGUCCUCCUGGACAAACCUCCCCGGUCCCCGCGCCAUCGCCGCGGCCACGAGCAGCGCCGCGGGUCGCCCCGCCCAGACCUCCGCGCCCGGAGCUCAGGCUCCGUCCUCUUCCCCAAGGAGCUGCUAAUCACGCCCCAGGGACGUUGGCCUCUGGGGGAGGGGAGGACCCUAGGCCUGCGCCCGACUGCUGGGAGGCGCCCCGCCCUCCCUCCUCCUGCUCACCCCUCUCAGCUUCUCUCCCUUUUCUUCUCCUCCCCACUCAGCUCCGUUUUCUCUCCACACCCAGUCCCUUGUCCCCUCUUCGCUCACUCCACCCCACUUUCCUUCUUCCCUACGCAGUGGGUCCCUCUCCCCCUUUCCUCUCCCCUACAACCUCCCUCUCCACUCCCUACCGGCCCUCUCCCCUCCCCCACCCCGUACCCUCUGCCCCGCCUCCCCAUUCGGGUCACCCCGUCCCAGUCCCCUCUUCUCCCCUCCUCCGCCCCUCCCUCCUUCUCCUCUCCCCUCUCCUGUCCCACUCCGUCCUCCCCCCUCCUCCGCACCCCGCCCGUCCCCUGGUCCCCGCCCCGCAGUGUCCUGGCGCCGGCGUAACCGCUCGUCCCACCUCCCUCCCAGCCAAUCGCUCCUCUCCUCCGCUCGGGGACGCUCCCCCGGGGAAUCCUGUGGCUGGAGAUGCUCGGUCGAGUCCCUGGUAUGUGGUCACCGUGCGGGGGCCGCUGCGGGUGCGGAAUCCAGACCCGGGGGUGUAGCAACCUCACAACUCCCUGUGCAGAAGAAAGCAGAAGAUCGGGGCGCGGGUCCAGGGUGGUCCGCACAGCCGUGGUUUAGCCGAGGGCGGCGCGCUACACUUAGUCUCUUGUGCAGUGCUUUCUGGCCACAGCAGCUUCCCUAGAAGUGACCCCACUUGGGUCAGAACCACCCAGCUGGGCCGCUGAUAUUUCCCCCUUUCGCAGAGGGAGCAGCGCGCGUCGGGAGACGCAGUGACUCGCCAGGGUCAGACCCAGAGCUUCUUCCCCACGCAAGGCCGAGGGCAGGGUGAGCACAGGGGCGUUCUCCGUCUGCCCCGGCUCGGGUGCACUGGCCUGGACGCCUCUGUGCAGGUUCCAUGGUGUAGAGAGACGGCUCGAGUGCAGGCGGAGUUUAAGGGAAGGGGGUUUUGACUGCGGGAGCCGACAGAAAGGACUAAAUCCAAAAGGUCCUCUUGGACCUGAACCUUCUGCUACAAGCCUGACCGAUAAAAGGGGACUCUGCAUCUUUUUAAGCCCAAAAUAGAAAAGCCUUGGGAGUUAGAAUGGCAGAAACCCCAGACCGACGGCGCUGGAAGCGCGCAGCUCGGUGCAUUCCCCGGCCGCACUGCCCUGCGGGGCCGCGCACGUUCCAGCGCUCAGGGACGGUGCCGCAGGACACACCCCAAACACAGAGCACAGACGAGGUAAAAACGAGCCGGCUGCACCAGGGACCACGCUGCCCCUAGCUGGCUCUGCCCCAGCCUCUCUGAACAGCAGGUCCCUGCGUCGAAGCCCGAGGGUCUUCGCAUUUGCUGCUGUGGCUUCUCCCGGAUACCCACCCCCUUCAGAUCUUACAGAAGGGCCUUCUUCCAAACCAGACCUUCCCUGUUCCCUGGCAACUGGUUUUAAAAUCACAGCACCUCUGCUCCUGCAAUUCACAGUCCCUCCUCAGUCCCUUCACUGCUUAGUUUUUUUUUCCUUAGCCCUUGCCGCAGUCAAACUCGAAUGCGUUUGUGAAUCACCUGAGGACCUUCCUACAACACAGAUGCGAAUUCACUUGGUCGAGGGUGGGUCCCCAAGUUUCUAACGCGUGUCCGUGAUAUUCUGCUGCUCCCCACCUGCCUGCGGAUCUGCGAGGACCUUUGACUUACAAAGGGUCCAACAUGCAGAUAAUACAAAAGUUUAUUUUUCCUAUGUAUUUUGGUUUACCAUCCCCCGAACUUGAAUGUGAGUUCCACCAGGAUAGAGCUCUGGUCUGUUUUGUUUGCUGCUAUAUUCUCUGUACCUGGAACAGGCCUGGCACAUAGUAGGAGCACUAUGUUAUUUCCAGAAGGAAGCAGUGAAUGAAAUACAAACCAGAAAAGACAGCAGAGGUGAUAAACCUAACAUUAUACAAAGUGAAAGUCAAGGUGCAAAUUAUGAACGAAACAAAGGUUUUACACUCAUUUUUAAAAGGGAGAAAUAACAGUCACAAGCCCUUAGGUCCUAAAGUAAAAACUGUCUCCCCAAAAAAGGAAAAUUGCAAAUACUACAUUGAUUUUAGAAAGGUUAACUCCCAUCUUGGUCACAUCUCAGAAGCAAAAAGUGACGUAAAAGACUUGAAUAAAGAAAUUAAUGGCCAGGCGUGGUGGCUCAUGCCUGUAAUCCCAGCACUUUGGGAGGCCGAGGUGGGCAGAUCACUUGACGUCAGGAGUUUGAGACCAGCCUGGGCAACAUGGGGUAACCCCGCCUCCACUAAAAACGUAAAAAUUAGCUGGGUGUGGUAUCAGGCACCUGUAAUACCAGCUACUCAGGAGGCUGUGGCAAGAGAAUCAGUUGAACCUGGGAGGCAGAGGUUGCAGUGAACUGAGAUUGUGCCACUUCACUCCAGCCUGGGCAACAGAGUGAGACUCGUCAAAAAAAAAAAAAAAAAAAAAAAGAAUAAACAGGACCUGUGUAUUUACUAGUU